UGUGGAUGCAGUAAGCAUAGUAACUAUGUCCCAGAGUGCUAUAACAUUUUUAUGGUCUCUUUUAUUUCUCAAGGAGUUUCAUCUCCUUGUAUACCUGCUUAUCUUUGAUUGUGUGCUGGUCAUUGUGUUUGAAAAAGUGUUUCUAGCAGUCAUUAUAGGUUAGGUAAGGAUUUUUUUCAUUGCUUUUGCCAGACACUUGGGAUCACUUUUAUUCUAAUAAAAAGUUGAGAGUCUAUGCAAUAAUUGGUUUAGUUUGCUUCUAAGUUUUUCUUUCUCAUGGGAUUCAGUUUUUUGCUUAUUCUGAAGCAGAGAUGGCUCCCUUGGUGGAUCCUGUACUCUGACAUUUUGUCCUCCUAGCCUUGAAGACUGCCAAAGUGUGGUUUAGACUCUUAGGCACCUCUUUGAUUAGGCAAACGUUUACCUAAAGAAGCCUCAAGGUUCCUUGCUUUCUAUUUCAGAUUUCUGUCUUCUCUUCGGAUGGUGGCUGGUAAUUUCACACUGUCUUGUUAGCUGUUUGAUAUCCUUCCUCCUUUUUUUAAAUAAGGAAUACACAUAUAAUGUACACUAAUCUUAACUGUAUACUCUGAAUAAUUUUUAUAAAUGUAGUUGACUGUGUAAUCACUCACAUAACAUACAGUAGUCCUCCUUAUCUGCAGUUUCACUUUCCUUGGUUUCAGUUCCUGCAAUAUAGUAUGAGAAGAUACUUUGAGAGAUGGAGAAGACUACCUUUUAUUACAGCAUAUUAUUAUAAUUAUUUUAUUAGUUAUUAUUUAUCUCUUAGGUAGAAGGGUCUGAUUGUGAAGCAGUACACUAAUUUUUAAAGCAGAAUUUUAGAAUACAUUUUCAAAGUAGUGCUGAGAUUCUGUUGCUGUAAUUGCUGAAGAUAAAUUUCUGGAAUUUUUUUAGAAAUUGUUCUUUGGAGAUACUGAGUUGUAUCCCUUAUCAGUUUAUAUCACAUUUUGAUCCAGUGUUUUAUUAUCAGUUUGAAUUCUGAGCUCAUUCACCAGACUUGCUUGGGAAACAUUUAUUCUAUCACAAAAAAUUAUUUUCCUCCAAGGUUGAUGAUUUGCCCUCAUUGAGGCUUACCAAAAGAAUGCCAUCCAAAUUCUCCCCUGAAACUGAGGGUUACCUCUGACUACUUCACUGUCAGUAGUCUCUUUGACUUUCUUUUAAGUGAUAGUUGGAUCUGCCCCAUUAAAAAAUACAUAUAACCAACAUUUUAGACCAGCUUGUUUUAGCUGGUUUAAUGUAAUGAUUUAGGUUGAUCUUCCUUAUACCGCUAAGGAAAUUAGAACCUGAGUUACCCAUUGAAUUAAAAUUAGUUUUAAGAUAAUAAAUCAUACAGUGCUAGAAAGAGAACUUAAAAAUUAUGUUUCAGUUUUCUUCUUUUAUGAGACCAAAAAUGGAUCAGUACUAACGUGUGAACCAAAUAAGAUAUUUAGUUUACCAGCACACUCUUUUAUGCAUAAUUCCACAGCAACUCUCAGUGGUAGGUAGGCUGAAAAUUUUAACUCUCAUUUUACACACAAAGAAACUGAGGGUCAGGGAAGUGAAGUGACUUGGUCUGAAUUCCUAGAGCUGGUUAAUGGCAGAGUUGUAACACAUUUGCAUUGAGGACUUCCUAUAUGUUGAGUGAUUUCCCUGCAAGGCUUAUAGUCCACCAUUGUACUGCUGAAUUCCAGUUUUAUUGACAUCCUACAGGAAUUUUCCUCUCUUCACCUGUGUGUAUUUACACCUCUUGGUCCAUAAGUUUUCCGAUUUUCACUCAGUACAGGGCCUUUAUAUAGCCUUGACUGUCACUCUGGUUGCCCUUAGCACUUUUAUUCUGAAUAUGUUCUGUUAGCUGCAGAUGGCUGGAACCAAGCUUGUCUUGAUUGUUUUAUCCCAAGGCCCUUGAGCAGUUUUUGCGUGUUGUGGAGCUGAAUUAAUAUCUAUUAAAUGAAUAGAUGAAUACAUUCUUGUAUUUAGAAUCCAAUUAGAUAUAGAUUUUUGAAGAUAGGGCCUGGAAUUAUUUACUCUUUUCUUUGUAUUUUUCAUGGUGUCUGCUAUAGUGCUUAUUGUUACAGUUGGCAGUCUGGAAUUUUUAACUGACUUUUAAAAUGAUGUCGGACUCCUGAACACCAGAUAUAUUGUAUCCUUCAUUUUAACUUUUAUCUAUGGAGCACAGGCAUUAUGUGCAGUUCUGAUAUGAUGUAUCAAGUAGAUUAGGCACAUAUACCAUGUAAACUAAUUAUAGGUCAUUUUUAAAAGGCCCUGACUCUGUAACUGAUAGAAGUAGGGAAGACUUGGAAUGGACAUUUGUUUUCCUAAAUACCUGAAGUUGUCAUGUUGACCAGUAUAAACCUACUCGGAUUUGAUAAGUCUGUCUGGAAACCUACCUGUGGAAGGGGAAAUUUGACCUCAUUCUUAUCUCAUGCCUCAUUAACAUACAAGUGUAAAGAAACCGAUGAAACCAGAUGAUUGCUCAUUUUGCUCUUAGGCCCAUCUCAUUCUUUGAUCUUAUUAGCAGGAAGUACUUUGUUGAUUUAGUGAAUAGCGUAAACAAACCUCCUUUCUCUCUAGCAAUGACAGAAGAUUUGCUUUACUUUUGCGCUGAGAAAAUACUUAAAGCUGUAGAAAUGUGACGUUAUGUUUCACGGGGUUGCAGCAAGAGCAUUCUUUAGGGAAAGCAUAAGAACUGUGAAAGUACAGUGUUGAGACUUUCUCUGUUAGUGAAUAAUGACUUUAAUAUUAACUGAAAUAAUUUCUAAUGAGAAGAUAUGACAGGUUGAGUAUCUCUUACCUGAAAUGCUUGGGACCAGAAGUGUUUCAGGUUUUAGAUUUUUUCAGAUUUUGGAAUAUUUGCAUUAUACCAGUUGAGCAUCCCAAAAAUGAAAUCCAAAGUGCCCUAAUGAGCGUUUCCUUUGAGUGUCACGUCAGUGCUCAAAACGUGUCUGAUUUCAGAAAGUUUAGAUUUGGCAUACUCAACCAGCACCUGGGAGUCUGCCCUGACAUAUAUUUGAACUAAUGAACCGUGAAUCUCAAUGAAGGAAGGAGGGUACUGAAAUUACUGUGCUGUACAUUCCAUGAUGCGAGAGACUUGGCUUUGUUCUUGGCAGUGUCUGCGGUGCCUAGUACACUGCCUGGCUCAUAAUAGCUACUCGGUAAAUACUGAAUGAAUGAAUAGUAAGAUUUAUUAUGCAUUAUACAUUAUAUAUUUAUUGUAAUACAUAUUAUAUAUUAUACAUAGUAAAUCCUUCCUGUUAUCUAUGUUAUUAUCUGCCUGUUUUAAAUUUAAAAACAGAACAUUAAUCAUUUAAGUAUUGAGUUAUAGCCUUUGAGGAAACAAAUGUAGCUUGGUUGAGGCAUCAUUUCUGAUGCUUUUUUCUUUCUGACUUGAUGAGAAAGUUGCGUUAAAUACGUUGCUCGUUGUUUAUUCAUUCAUUGUCAUUGAAUUUCUUUAAGACAUUUUAAAUGAGUACAUGAGAAUCUAUUAAAUGUGAAUUAACAAUGUAGUCAAUCCCUUGUUAUUUGGACGUGUGUGUGUGUGUAUAUGUAUGUAUAUGUAUGUAUAUAUAUUGCUAUUACAAAUAAUACAUCAAUGAAGGACAUUUUCUUCUUUUUUUUUCUUUCUUUUUUAGGGGGUAGGACAGUUCACUAAAUAGCAACUUAGAAAAACAGGAUCUAGGAAUUUCUGUGAAAAAAUGAGCUGGGAUUAUACAGCUGUGAAGGUGAGAUCAGAAGCUUUAGUGGUCAGACAGCUGAGAUAAGACAGCACAAAUGAUACAACUCUUGGUUAGCCAGCUCCUUCUCCACGUAGAUAAUGUAUAAUCAUCAGUCUUCACAUAAAAGCUAUCUUGCAAUUUGUGUUGGAAUGGCUAUCACUUGUGUUUGUCUUUUACUUUUAAGGAACAAAUGAACCACUACAACUCUUUUGGCCUCUUAAGCAUGGCUUAAAGAUUGUAAAUGCAUUUAACCCCUUUAUAUAUGUGGUUACAUAUAUUAAUGUUACUUUUAUAAUUUCCUUUCUGCAUUUCAUUGGAAAAGUUUUGGUUUUUCAUAUUAAAAUACUGUAAAAUAUAUUCAUACAAAGACUAUGUGUAAUAUGUUACAUAAAGACUGACAUAAUGAUGUCCAUCCCAUCCUCUCCUCAGUUUAAGUGAAAGAACAUUCCCAGUACCCUCCUGGAUCACCUCUGUCUACCUCCAUCCUACCACUGGCUUGAGGAAACCAUCGGCAUCACUGUGGGCUCUGGCAUUCCUUUGCUUUUCUUUAUAGACAUGUAUUCCUCUGAGAAACCUUGGACAGCAGAUUUUGGUUUAAUAUCUGAUUGGGACAACAUUCAGACCCAUUUCCAGUCAUGACCACACUUAAUCCUUGUCCUCAGAGAUACGUGAUGACUGCUGCGUCUUCAUCCUUAGGUCCAAGAGCCAAGCAAGAAGAAAAAGAUUCAGACCAGGAUGUAGCACUCAAACUUGCCCAGGAGCGAGCUGAAAUAGUUGCUAAAUAUGACAGAGGACGAGAAGGUGCAGAGAUUGAACCUUGGGAAGAUGCUGAUUACCUUGUUUACAAAGUCACAGAUAGAUUUGGCUUUUUACAUGAGGAGGAGCUCCCAGAUCAUAAUGUGGCUGUGGAACGGCAAAAGCACCUGGAAAUUGAAAGAACUACCAAAUGGCUGAAAAUGCUGAAAGGAUGGGAAAAAUACAAGAACACUGAAAAGUUUCAUAGGCGAAUUUACAAAGGAAUACCACUCCAGCUCAGAGGUGAAGUCUGGGCCCUCCUUCUUGAGAUCCCUAAAAUGAAAGAAGAAACAAGGGACCUGUAUAGUAAAUUAAAACACAGAGCACGGGGCUGUUCACCUGACAUCAGACAAAUAGACCUGGAUGUCAACCGCACAUUUCGGGACCACAUUAUGUUUAGAGACAGAUAUGGUGUUAAGCAACAAUCCUUAUUCCAUGUGCUUGCUGCCUAUUCUAUUUAUAACACGGAAGUCGGGUAUUGUCAGGGGAUGAGCCAGAUCACAGCUUUACUCCUCAUGUAUAUGAACGAGGAAGAUGCCUUCUGGGCCCUGGUCAAACUCUUCUCAGGCCCUAAACAUGCCAUGCAUGGCUUUUUUGUCCAAGGUUUUCCUAAACUCUUGAGGUUUCAAGAACAUCAUGAAAAAAUACUGAACAAAUUUCUGUCCAAGCUUAAGCAACACUUGGAUUCUCAAGAAAUCUACACAAGUUUUUACACAAUGAAAUGGUUUUUUCAGUGUUUCCUUGAUCGUACUCCCUUUACACUAAACCUCAGAAUAUGGGAUAUCUACAUCUUUGAAGGAGAACGAGUUCUUACUGCUAUGUCUUACACCAUCUUAAAAUUACACAAAAAACAUCUAAUGAAAUUGUCCAUGGAAGAACUUGUAGAAUUUUUUCAGGAGACCCUGGCAAAGGAUUUUUUCUUUGAAGAUGAUUUUGUGAUAGAGCAACUUCAGAUUUCUAUGACAGAACUAAAGCGGGCAAAGUUAGACCUUCCAGAACCUGGUAAAGAGGAUGAAUAUCCAAAGAAGCCCUUGGGGCAGCUUCCACCUGAACUUCAGUCUUGGGGCGUCCAUCACUUGAGCAACGGACAGAGGAGCGUGGGCCGGCCGAGCCCGCUGGCCAGCGGCAGGAGGGAGAGCGGGGCGCCCCACAGGAGGCACGAGCACUCCCCGCACCCCCAGAGCAGGACCGGGACGCCCGAGAGAGCACAGCCGCCAAGACGGAAAUCGGUGGAGGAGGAGAGCAAAAAGCUUAAAGAUGAGGCAGAUUUUCAAAGAAAACUCCCAUCGGGUCCACAGGACAGUUCCAGGCAAUAUAAUCACGCAGCUGCCAACCAAAAUAGCAACGCCACUUCAAAUAUCAGGAAGGAGUUUGUGCCCAAAUGGAAUAAACCGUCAGACGUCUCAGCUACAGAGAGAACUGCCAAAUACACCAUGGAAGGCAAAGGUCGAGCAGCGCACCCCGCGCUCGCAGUUACCGUCCCAGGUCCUGCCGAGGUGCGGGUGUCAAACGUGCGGCCAAAGAUGAAGGCCCUGGAUGCUGAGGACGGGAAGCGGGGCUCCACUGCAUCGCAGUACGACAACGUGCCAGGCCCGGAGCUGGACAGCGGCGCUUCCGUGGAGGAGGCGCUGGAAAGGGCUUACUCCCAGAGCCCCCGGCAUGCCCUUUACCCUCCUAGCCCGAGAAAGCACGCUGAGCCAAGUUCUAGUCCAUCAAAAGUAUCCAACAAGUUUACUUUUAAAGUACAGCCUCCAAGUCAUGCACGAUAUCCGUCCCAGCUAGAUGGGGAAGCCCGAGGGCUAGCUCAUCCCCCCUCCUACAGCAAUCCCCCCGUUUACCACGGAAACUCUCCCAAACACUUCCCUACUGCCAACAGCAGCUUUGCUUCUCCACAGUUUAGCCCUGGGACUCAACUGAAUCCUUCCAGGAGACCUCAUGGUUCUACUCUUUCCGUCAGUGCUUCUCCGGAGAAAUCUUACAGCCGCCCAAGCCCCCUUGUACUGCCGUCUAGUCGAAUAGAAGUCCUCCCUGUUGACACUGGUGCUGGGGGAUAUUCGGGCAAUUCAGGGUCACCAAAGAAUGGAAAAUUGAUCAUUCCACCAGUGGAUUACUUGCCAGAUAACAGAACAUGGUCAGAAGUUAGUUAUACAUACAGACCUGAGACGCAGGGACAAUCAUGGACCCGAGAUGCUAGCCGUGGCAAUUUACCAAAAUACUCAGCCUUUCAACUCGCACCCUUUCAGGACCAUGGCCUCCCUGCAGUUUCUGUAGAUAGUCCCGUGAGAUAUAAAGCUUCACCGGCCGCAGAAGAUGCCAGUCCAUCUGGAUAUCCAUAUUCAGGGCCCCCGCCUCCAGCCUACCACUACAGGAAUCGGGACGGGCUUUCCAUCCAAGAGUCAGUGUUGCUGUGAGAUUUGACGUGUACUUGCUAAAGACGAGAGAGAAACCACGUGAAACCUACAUUGCUAUGUUCAUAAUUGCCAAAGCAGUAUUUAUACUAUUGUAAACAACUCGCACAUCUCUCCUGUCUGUUAGUAGUAAGAAUACAGGGAAAUGUCUUCAGCCCCACGUAGAUGCUGCUUAAGAUGAGCGUUUCAAUUGCAUCAUCACUGACCUGUUAGAAUUUAACCCGGAAACAUCGCAAUAGCAUUUAGGGAUGCACGCACAGUGGUAAUUUAUUACUCAGUUCCGGUUAUGUUUUUCUCCAAAACCUGAACAUUUUUACUCUGUUGGCUCAUUCUAUUUUGACUAAUGUUACAAAGUACUGAAAAAACUGUAGAAUAGAUAUUUUUAAGGCUAUAUGUAGUGUAUGUGUCUUUUAAUAGAUAUAGGCAUCUGUUCAUCCACAUUUGAACACAGAGCUAAAGAAACGUUUUUUAAAAAACUACUUUUAAUCCAGAUCCAUGGAAUAAUAUGUAAUUCUUGUUUUCCUUGUCUUUUAGUCCAGUUUUUCUUUUUCCCUCUCAUAUAUUUGUAACCUGGGUCCUAAACUGACUGAAGAGUUUGUCCUGACUUUAUUAAUUGCAGUCUCACAGAAUGCUCAUCAUUCUCCUUCAGCUGUUGCCAUUUUCUUUCAAUCUGAAAAUUAAAGACAUUGGAGAGAAAGGCUAACCACUUAAUGGUGCUUAAAAAUCGGGGCACUUAAAAUAAGUUUACGGCCAAAGGUGCAGCAGUGCUUAUCACAUCCACAUACUAAGAGAUUGGUCUUAGUGCGUUUGUGCCCUUUGUUCUGGUCUGACUCUUGCGAAUCUCAGAGCAGGAGAAGUUGCAGCUUACUGAUCCCUCAGUGCUCACAGUACUCAUGUGGGGCAGCCACACUAACUGCAUUAGCAGUGUGGUUACUUCUUUCUUCUGCCUCGACUCACAUGGCUUCUCCCCACGAAGGUCCCAGGGUGGCCAUUUAUACAAUCCAUUUCUGUCCUCUUUAUGGAAUGUAGUCGACGGAUAUUGCUGCACCUCAUCAGGCCAUUACAUUGUCCAUGUUAAAAUUAUAAAAAUGAUCCUAGUUUUUCAUAGGAGUCUAGGAUUUUGAUCUUUUAAAAAAUACAGUGUGAUUUCAUGCUUUUGAACAUCUUUUUUUCAUUGAAACAAAUUCAAGUUCUUGGCUUAAAAAAAAAUUAGUGAUGUCUUUAAAAAAUAUUCUGUUACACUACAGAUACCAAAACACUGACAAAGAUUUAGGCACUCCAAGAGAGUAUGACUUCGUGUUUAAUUGGGGAGCUUGUUUUCAACAUUGCUUAUAUUUGAAUAGUAGAAAACCCGACAUUGAUGUUUCUUCCUGUUGCAAGGUGGGGCUUUAAACUUUCAAGGUACAAAAGUAUGUCUUUUAAAAUGGAAGUAACGUUUGUUUAGCUAGUGAAUGUGACAAUAUAUUUUAUGUAUAUAAUGAGUCUAAUGUAAUUUUGAUCAACUUGGUAAUGAUGUUAUUAAAUAGCAAAACAAGUGCAGUGUAUUAAAGCUAAACACUACAUUGAAACGCAAACAAAAUUCUGGUGAAAUAACUGGGCUGUUGAUGCAGGUCAGGUGGAAGCUGAGAAAUAAAUGUAUAUAAAUAUGUAGCUGAGGAUAUUAAUUCCCAUUAUAUAACCAUAAUUCUGUGACUUGUAAUAAACCAAGCUGUACAAUUUAGUUUAUAAUAGCAGUAUCUGAGCUGCUCCAAAAUAUAUAUAUCAACAGUGGUAAAUACUGUAGAUUUUUAUAUAUAUAUAUAUAUAUAUAUAUAUAUAUGCAAAAAAUAUAUAUAUACACACAAGCACUAUUUUCUUAUGUCAUUUAUGACAUUUUUUAUCUGUAUACUUUUUUGAUGUGAUUGUUUUUUAACAUGCUAAAAGUAAUAAGUAUA